AUUUUCGGCGGCGGGAGCGGCGCAGGCGGCCGAGCGGGACUGGCUGGGUCGGCUGGGCUGCUGGUGCGAGGAGCCGCGGGGCUGUGCUCGGCGGCCAAGGGGACAGCGCGUGGGUGGCCGAGGAUGCUGCGGGGCGGUAGCUCCGGCGCCCCUAGCUGGUGACUGCUGCGCCGUGCCUCACACAGCCGAGGCGGGCUCGGCGCACAGUCGCUGCUCCGCGCGCGCGCCCGGCGGCGCUCCAGGUGCUGACAGCGCGAGAGAGCGCGGCCCUCAGGAGCAAGGCGAAUGUAUGACAACAUGUCCACAAUGGUGUACAUAAAGGAAGACAAGUUGGAGAAGCUUACACAGGAUGAAAUUAUUUCUAAGACAAAGCAAGUAAUUCAGGGGCUGGAAGCUUUGAAGAAUGAGCACAAUUCCAUUUUACAAAGUUUGCUGGAGACACUGAAGUGUUUGAAGAAAGAUGAUGAAAGUAAUUUGGUGGAGGAGAAAUCAAACAUGAUCCGGAAGUCACUGGAGAUGUUGGAGCUCGGCCUGAGUGAGGCACAGGUUAUGAUGGCUUUGUCAAAUCACCUGAAUGCUGUGGAGUCCGAGAAGCAGAAACUGCGUGCGCAGGUUCGUCGUCUGUGCCAGGAGAAUCAGUGGCUACGGGAUGAACUGGCCAACACGCAGCAGAAACUGCAGAAGAGUGAGCAGUCUGUGGCUCAACUGGAGGAGGAGAAGAAGCAUCUGGAGUUUAUGAAUCAGCUAAAAAAAUAUGAUGACGACAUUUCCCCAUCCGAGGACAAAGACACUGAUUCUACCAAAGAGCCUCUGGAUGACCUUUUCCCCAAUGAUGAAGACGACCCAGGGCAAGGAAUCCAGCAGCAGCACAGCAGUGCAGCCGCGGCUGCCCAGCAGGGCGGCUACGAGAUCCCCGCGCGGCUGCGGACGCUCCACAACCUGGUGAUCCAGUACGCCUCGCAGGGGCGCUACGAGGUAGCUGUGCCCCUCUGCAAGCAGGCCCUGGAGGACCUGGAGAAGACUUCAGGACACGACCACCCGGACGUGGCCACCAUGCUCAACAUCCUGGCCUUGGUGUACAGGGAUCAGAAUAAAUACAAAGAUGCAGCUAACCUACUGAAUGAUGCCUUGGCUAUUCGUGAGAAAACUUUGGGCAAAGAUCAUCCUGCGGUGGCGGCGACUUUGAAUAACCUUGCAGUCCUUUAUGGUAAAAGAGGGAAGUACAAAGAAGCAGAGCCGUUGUGUAAAAGAGCUCUGGAAAUCCGAGAAAAGGUUUUGGGGAAGGAUCACCCCGAUGUUGCCAAGCAGUUAAAUAACUUGGCCUUACUGUGCCAGAACCAGGGCAAGUAUGAAGAAGUAGAAUAUUAUUAUCAAAGAGCCCUCGAGAUCUACCAGACAAAACUGGGACCUGAUGACCCCAACGUGGCUAAGACGAAAAAUAACCUGGCAUCCUGCUAUUUGAAACAAGGAAAGUUCAAGCAAGCAGAAACACUGUACAAAGAGAUUCUCACUCGUGCACAUGAAAGGGAGUUUGGUUCUGUAGAUGAUGAAAAUAAACCCAUCUGGAUGCAUGCUGAAGAAAGAGAAGAAUGCAAAGGAAAGCAAAAGGAUGGGACAUCUUUUGGAGAGUAUGGCGGCUGGUACAAAGCCUGCAAAGUUGAUAGUCCAACUGUUACAACCACUCUAAAAAACCUUGGGGCACUUUACAGACGUCAAGGCAAAUUUGAAGCUGCAGAAACGUUAGAAGAAGCUGCUAUGAGGUCUCGUAAACAGCGAAGUAUCUCAGAAAUACCUAAGAAAAUCUUAAGUGCUAAUGGGUCAAACCAUUUUCCCCUGCCUGGCUCACAGGGUCUUGACAAUGUUCACAAACAGAGGGUGGCAGAAGUGCUCAAUGACCCUGAGAACAUGGAGAAGCGCAGGAGCCGUGAGAGCCUCAACGUGGACGUGGUCAAGUACGAGAGUGGCCCUGACGGAGGGGAGGAAGUGAGUAUGAGCGUAGAGUGGAACGGGGAUGGCACUGGAUCUUUAAAACGCAGUGGUUCCUUUAGCAAACUCCGGGCUUCCAUUAGACGCAGCAGUGAGAAGCUGGUUAGGAAGCUGAAGGGAGGAAGUUCACGAGAGAGUGAGCCAAAGAACCCCGGCAUGAAGCGUGCCAGCUCUCUGAAUGUCCUUAACGUGGGUGGCAAGGCUGCUGAAGAUCGCUUUCAAGAACGAAAUAAUUGUCUGGCCGACUCGCGAGCUCUGAGUGCCAGCCACACUGACCUGGCCCACUGAGAGCCAGCAGGGCUAGGUAACCUGUCUUGGGAGUGUGAGACCGCCCCGCCCUGCCACGCCCCUCACCGCCCUGCCCGGAGGCGCCAGCCGCACUCCUUGGCUUCCUUUCCUAGAUAGUGACGUCCACCAACCUUGGAGGUGCCUUUUCAAAACACCCGGGAGGCCGUGCCUCAGCAUUCUGUUACUCGGCCUGCAGCCCCAGUGCCAGGAGCCACCCCGACCGCGACCCGGCCAGGCUGGCUCAGGGAGGCCGAGGUGGCGCUGAGGUGGCUUCAGCACGCUGGGGAUUGGCUCCUGCUCACGGAUGCUGUUGCAUUUCCUGCCUGCCACCUUUUUGCCAUGACACCAGACUCUCUUUUAAAUUGUAAUAUUGUAAUAAGGCUGUAAAUUAAGAAUCUGGAAACAUAAAGUACCCCUUUCAGAACGAUAGGCAUUUAGUGAUCUAUGGCAGUAAAGCCUGAAGCUUAGCGGACACUGGUCAGUGGGAAGUGAAUUCCUUCCCAGCUGGAGCAUCUUCCGGGUCUCUCUUUCCAAGGUCCCCAUGCCUGUGGCCCUGGGGCCCCAUGCCCCCUUUUGAGCUGUGUUCUCCCGGACGCCCCUGCACACGAAGCCCAUAGAGACGUGUGUUUCACUUUUUUUUUUUUUUUUUUUGAGACGGAGUCUAACUCUGUUGCCCAGGCUGGAGCGCAGUGGCCCAAUCUCGGCCCACUGCAAGCUCCACCUCCUGGGUUCACGCCAUUCUCCUGCCUCAGCCUCCCGAGUAGCUGGGACUACAGGCACCCGCCAGGCGGAUCACAAGGUCAGGAGAUCGAGACCAUCCUGGCUAACAUGGCGUUUCACUUUUUAAAAGCUUAAGCUUUAUGGAAUGAGGGAGCACGGUGGACUCUGACAGGAACCUUUUCAAAUCAAUGCUGAGGCUGUAUUUCUUAGCCGUCCACAAACUAGUCCAUAGGUAAAGAGCAUACAAAACAGACGCCGAGGUGAUCAGUGAUUCCAAAGGCUGACGCUCAGCAGCGCCACCUCCAUGCCAGCCAACUAGGCUACGGGAUGGAGGGGCGGUCUGUGAAACACCAGCCAUCCCGUGAAAGCUCAGCUUGCCACUGUCAUGUAACAGGGUGGGUGGUGGCACAGCAGAGGCUCACACUUGUCACCUUCAGCCUCUAGAAGCUCCCCGUGGGGCACGAAGGCUGGGGACAGAGUGUCCUGAGGUUUUGUUACAAGGCUAGACUUUAAAAUACCUUUCAAAGUUUCAUCCCGCCUCAUGUCGCAGGACUGCUGUGUUUGUGAAAGCGCGUUUGUUUCCACAAGACAAGCUCCGUGUAGUCGCCAGCGGGUGCCUGGCCCAGGAGCUGCCCUGUGGAGCCAGCGUUGUCCCCGAGCUGCUCGCCUGUGGCCGUGGCUCCUUUUCUGAGGCUCCUGACUCCAUUCUUGCAGAUUCUGGUGGAUCAGGAGCUUACAUUCUAAAUGCUACAUAGAGGUGUUGAAGAAAAUUUCAUAGGUUCUGUAAUAGUGGAUGGGAUUAAAAGAAAAAAUGUUAAAUUAUAUAUAUAUAUAUGGCUGGGUGCGGUGGUUCAUGCCAGUAAUCCUAUAAUCUUAGCACUUUGGGAGGCUGAGGCGGGAGGAUCACUUGAGCCCAGUUCAAGAACAGCUUGGGCAACACAGCGAGUCCCUGUGUCUAGCAAAAAAAACCAUGUGUAUAUAUAUAUAUAUGUGUGUGUGUGUAUAUAUAUAUAUAUAUAUAUACAUACAUAUAUAUACAUAUAUAAUUUGAUGGGUUGUGAGAAGCCAACCCCCCCCAAAAAAAGGGGGGUGUAGAGCAGCUUCCCCUGACAGGUGCCGUGGCUGCCCCCGUAGUGGGCUAUGUCUGUGCACAGGCGACAGGGAGGAGGGCUCCGGAGCUUCCCUUGUGGUGGGGGUGCCUUCUCCCUGUGAGGAUGCUGAGCAGAGUUUGGAACCCAGACAGUUUCCCUUAGUGACAGUUAUCUGGAAAGGAAAAAGGGCAUUUAGAAGGAAUAAACAUAGGGCUGAAUAUGGAGUUGAAUUUUAACCUCUUCAGACUGAUGGGUGCAGACGAGGUUGUGUGGGGCCUCUGUGGAGCCUGCUGUGGCUUCCAGCCAUGGGACUUUAGGGCCGAGGUGGCCUCUGCAGCACUGUGGCUGUGGGAGCACUGUGUGUUGGGGUAAGAGAAGCCAGGGGGCCUCCCUGAAGCCAGCUCAUAAAGGAAGGUUCGUGUUUCAGAGGGAGGCGGCAAGGGAAUCUGAGUACCUGAGUCCCCGAUGUUUGAACCCUUCCACCCAAUAGAAGUGCGGUGAUUUCAGCCAUUUCCCAUCUGGCGGUCUGAAUUUUUCCCUUCAGAGGAGAGAAGUGGUGGGCCCAGGCAUCCCUCCUCCUGUGUGUGGUCGUUCUGGUGAGAGGAACCCCACGCGAGAGUCAGCACCUGUUUCUUCAGAGUUGCUGUCAAAAUAAUCACUGCGCCCCCGCCCCCCGCCCCCCCCCACAGCAGCCGUGUGUGCAGCGCCCGUCCCCAGCAACCAUGGCAUGGGAGCGUCUGGAUCUGUGGGCGGACAGCAUAUCUCUGGGUAGUUGGUGCAGCUGUGGCAGAAAUCAGGCCCCUGGGGAAGUCCUGUGACAUGGAUGCUUCCCUGAAGCAGCAGCAGUGUGUGGCUCAGGGGUCCUCAGAGGCCGGUGGUGCCCGCGGGUGGCACGGGGCACUCUCAUGGGCAGCACUUGGUCUUGUGUUUACAGUAUUGGAGGGAUUCACAUCGUUGUUUUCUGGAUUAAGCUGCUAGGAGUAUCAUGUACUUAGAAAUUCAGUGUUUAUAGUAAGAUGUAUUAAACAUUGCUAAUGAUGUAUCGUUACAAUGUAUAACAGGUUUUCCAUUGUCAUAACUGUAUGGAAUUUUCUUGGAGGAUGUCAUUAGCUUCUGUUUGCACUGACUUGUGAGCUGUGUGUACGCUGUGGUCAGAUUUCUGAAUGCUGUAGAGCACUUACCAGCUCUGACCGUGUCUUGCUGGGGCCAGCAGGCUGCGUGUGCAGCGGGGCCAGCUGUCUCAGGGCUGAUAUGUAGACGUGUAUUCUGUUUACAAUUAGUUCCCCAACUCUGUGGGGAAGAACUUAAGCGGUUUUAGUGUUUUAUAAUAUGGUGAGGCAAUGAGGGUCAGGGCGCGUGGUCCCUGAGGGAGGGUCUUCAGGGCAAGACCCAUGGCCCUGGCCUGGAACUGUGCUCCCCAGGGCGUGGUGCCUCCCUAAGGGGAUGGUCAGUGUUCUGGGACUGACUGCCAGGCCAGCCCGUCUGCAGACUCCUGUGGUGGGAGUUCCCUGGGACGGGAAGCCCCUCGGCCCCUUCCCUCCAGGGGCAGGAACUGAGCCAGCAUGGGCGGGGCCGGCCGAGCUUCCAGGCGUGUUUUCUCUGUUAAAUGUACCUCUGUCUUUAAGCUGUCUCAUUUUCUAAUCGCUGGCAUGUCUUGCCUAGAAAAGCAUUUGGAAUUGCUUAUGUUCAAUUACAGAAAUAAAAUGUCUUACUUGCCAUUGUAGAA